CCCGCCCCCGCCUGGAGUCCGACGUGGAAGUUGCUGGCUGACUGGGCUUGCGAGGAAACCGCCUCGGAGCUGCAGCCGAAGGCCAAGGAAUCACUGAAGAUCGGCGAGGGAGGACAGGGGGUUCAUCAUGGGUGGCUUUUUCUCAAGUAUAUUUUCCAGUCUGUUUGGAACUCGGGAAAUGAGAAUUUUAAUUUUGGGAUUAGAUGGAGCAGGAAAAACCACAAUUUUGUACAGAUUACAAGUGGGAGAAGUUGUUACUACUAUACCUACCAUUGGAUUUAAUGUAGAGACGGUGACGUACAAAAACCUUAAAUUCCAAGUCUGGGAUUUAGGAGGACAGACAAGUAUCAGGCCAUACUGGAGAUGUUACUAUUCAAACACAGAUGCAGUCAUUUAUGUAGUAGACAGUUGUGACCGAGACCGAAUUGGCAUUUCCAAAUCAGAGUUAGUUGCCAUGUUGGAGGAAGAAGAGCUGAGAAAAGCCAUUUUAGUGGUGUUUGCAAAUAAACAGGACAUGGAACAGGCCAUGACUUCCUCAGAGAUGGCAAAUUCACUUGGGUUACCUGCCUUGAAGGACCGAAAAUGGCAGAUAUUCAAAACGUCAGCAACCAAAGGCACCGGCCUUGAUGAGGCAAUGGAAUGGUUAGUUGAAACAUUAAAAAGCAGACAGUAAUUCAGUCCAUUCUUCUCCCCUGAAAUGAAGACUACAUCACCUCUCUCCCUUUGGAAACAGUCAAGUGUACUUCACACUACUAGAUGUUAAAACUAUAUGAUUAUUGGCAUAUACUGACUGACUGCAAUAUUUGUAGUAAAUAGGGAAAAUAAGUAUUUAGUUGGAGGGAUAAUUUGAUCGAAUCACCUGAAUGUUCUAUGUAAUGUAAAAUAUUCUUUUCUUGCUUUCUUGUGUUAAGGUAUAUAUUCUAUUUGUAUGGAAUUCUUAUUCAAAUACAGUUCUAUUAAAGAGUAUACUCCUAUUGGAUGAAAAAAACCUAUUUUUGAAUAGUAGUUGCAGCUUGUUUGUAUAAAUACUAAAAAAUAUCUUAACAGAUUUUUUUCCCCUUAAAAUGAAUUAUCUUUCCAAAGAUUAGACUCAGUAUGAGAGUAGGUGAGGAACAUAGUUUGUGUAAUAUAAUCUUUAUUUGCUUACCUGACCACUUUUUAUUAAGCUGUUUUGUUUAAAAGCUUUUGGUUAUAGGCAUGAAUAUUGUUUUGAUGGUUAACUUCACUGACUUAUCUGUAAGUGUCAUUUUAUAGUACUUUACAGUUGUCAAAAAAAAUCUUACAUAUAUUGAUCUAGUUGAUCGGUAGAGGAAGCUUGUGAAGUAGGUAGGACAGGUUAUGAUGUCUUCACUGUAUGGACGUGAACCCAGGGUUCUAAUAGGUUGGCUUGCCCAAGGUCACCUGCUAGCUUGUAAGGUAGGAAUAGGGCUCAAAGUAAAACUUUUGGUUCAGAAGCUUGACUCAUAAACUAUACUAUAUAUUCCCAAAAAUGUCAGUAUUGACAACACAGUCUAACUCUUAAAUAAAAUUAUGCUAAUUAGUUACAUUCAAAAUAAUGUUUAUAAAUUUAUUUGUCUAUACUAGUAGAAGUGAUCAGUGACAUACUAUAAAUAAUCCUAAAUGGUUAUAUUUGAUAGAAUUCAUAACACAUUAAAGAGAAAAUUUCACAUUAAAGGAAGGUUUAAAAAUCUAUUUUCAGAUUAUAAAAGGUGUCUUUACUGGUUUUCAUUCCUUUUAUCUACAUGUAAUUGGACAUGUAAACUUGUUAAAAAUCAAAAUCUUACUGAUUGUACAGGGAGAAAUUAAGCAUUCUGUUUUAAAAAUUAGGCUUAUUGCUAGACUGUAAGUUUAAAAACAAUUCAUGUUCAAAGGAGCUUUUCAAAUUACCCAGUCCACCACAGAAUCAGCUAAUGUGACAGAAGUAAAUAUAGUGCGUCAUAAUUGCUAAAAACAGGGUGAAUUUCUUUCACUUAAGUUGGAAAACCAGCCUCUAAAAAAUUAGGUGCUGGUAAUGAGAGCUUAAUACCAUGGUUCCCUGCAGGUCUCAGAAACAUUAGUAGUUCCUUUCUUGGCCCUCACUGUCCUUCCAGUGUUGGCCUCUGGCCUCUUCCCCUCACAUUUAUGUUCAUUCUCCGGGCUUAUAUUCAUUCUCUGCUGCUUUCUCCCUUCACCCGUGGGACUCUCACCCUUCUUGCUCAUUCUCCAGCACCCAUUCCUACUUUAGUCUCUUUGAAAUCUUUUUUGGAGAUUUUCCUUCAGCUACAAAUGUUCCAGUACAACCAAUAUUACUCCUGAGGGGCAAAGACUUUUUCAUAUUUAUGUCCCUAGUAUCUGGUAUGGCGCCUGGCAUAUGGCAUUUCAGAAUAUGUUCAUAGUUGAAACAGUAGGAUAGAUAUUUGUCAUCUUGACAAGUAGCCCUUUGCAAUUUAUACUUGAGUUCACUCCUGGUCAAUGGCACAUGGCUGGAAAAUGCAGAAAGCAAGUUCACUUACAGCCUGAGGCUUAUAAAGCUUGUACAGCUGCCUCCCGGCAGUCCAGGAAAACUGCAAAAAAUGGGAAGUAAGGUCCUGGCAGGCAGACCCGGCAUGUAGCCGCUGGCCAUCUUGAAUCCUAGGGCAUGAAGUUGCCCCAAAGUUCAGCACUUGGUUAAGCCUGAUCCCUCUGGUUUAUCACAAAGAAUAGGAUGGGAUAAAGAAAGUGGACACUUAAAUAAGCUAUAAAUUAUAUGGUCCUUGUCUAGCAGGAGACAACUGCACAGGUAUACUACCAGCGUUUGGAUAUUGAUAUAUACAUGGCAAAUCUGAAUAUUGUUUUAUGAGAGGCCUGGCAAUGGGUAAAACACCAAACUUGAAAUCAGAACAUAGGUGCAAAUGGCCACUCCUGUAGUUUCUUUUCUGUAAAAUGGGAUCUGGACGAAUGAUACCAAACGUUUCUUUCUAACAUUGUAUUUUAUAACUCUGGCCUAUGAUUGUGUUGUGUCUUGCAUUAAAAAAAAAAAUUUGAGAGUGGUAGAAUUACUUCUGUUAUCUGAAAUACCUGAGAUGCACUUUAAACUGUUGAAAUGUAAGCUCUGAGGGCAGGGACCGUAUCUUAUUUACUGUUAGUAUCCGUUGCAUCUAGUGUGGUGCACCUGGCACACAGUAGGCACUCAAUAAAUAUGUAUUGAUUAAAAACAAAGACGUCUUCAAUAUGCCAGA